CCUUUAAUCUUUAUUUGCAUGACUACAUUUUAUGCAGUUGUAACCUUAAUGUACAUAUUUGGUAUUUUUUUCAAACAUGAAUUGAUUAGACAUUGUUGCUAUUUUGUAUCUAUUUUGUUAACAUAAGAACUUCCUGUGUUAUAUCAGAUUUUUUUUUUUUUUUUUUUUUUCUGAGACGGAGUUUCGCUCUUGUUGCUGCCCAGGCUUGAGUGCAAUUGUGGAUCUAGGCUCACCACAACCUCCGCCUCCUGGGUUCAAGCGAUUGUCCUGUCUCAGCCUACCGAGUAGCUGGGAUUACAGGUGCCCGCCACCAGGCCCGGAUAAUUUUUGUAUUUUUAGUAGAGACAGGGUUUCACUAUGUUGGCCAGGCUGCUCUCGAACUCCUGACCUCAGGUGAUCCACCCGCCUUGGCCUCCCAAAGUGCUGUGAUUACAGGCGUGAGCCACUGCGCCCGGCCUCUAUGUCAGACCUUAAUUAGCCAUUUCCUGUUAGUUAGAAUCCUGUGCCGCUCCUUCUUGCCUUUUACGGUGUUUGGAUAAUAUGCUGUGAAUACCUUUGUGCACUCAUUUCUUUAUUCAGGUCAUACCACUGAAACAUACUCCCCAGAAUAAAACUGAUGAUGAAAAGAUAGGAACAAUUUUAUACCUUGUCUUACAUAUUGCAAGAUUUUGCACUGCAUUGAUGUAUUGUUAACUUUGCAUGUUUGUCUUCUUUUUAAGCUCUCCUUGGAGAGUUUUUAAAUUUUCAGUACACUCCACAGGGUGGCCAAAGUAGAACUGCUUUGUCAUUGAGUAUAGGUUCAGUUAAAAACAACAAUCUGGCUCAGAGUUGAACACAAAGAAUCCAAUAAAUAUUAAUGGGUUAAUUUUCAGGUACCUUAGCCUUGACUUUCCUGUUUUCCAGAUUUCCCCUCCUUUUCCUUUUCGGUAUGUACUUCAUUAUUUAAAUGGGCAAUUUCGGGUUAGGCAGUUCUAGAUAGCGGUUCCCUUCCUGUGCCCGUUCUGGAACCUCUCUCGCCCUUCUGCGGUGCGAAAAAACCCAAUUCACAGCCGUCAUCGCCACUGAAGUUACACCCAGGGGUCGCUUCAAGAAGGAAACGUUUUCUUUAAGAAUUUCUAUGCCAGUGAAUUGGGGAAGGUUUUAAAGAUAACGGAGUUUGCCACGCGUUUCUGCCAAACAAUUCGACGUUGUGUAAAUCGCAGAAAUUCCAGGAAGGACUAACGACGUCCGUGGAUGAUUCUGCGGCUCACAGGCACACAGGACACGCUGGGUUUACCCUCCCGUGUCCCGACGGCACUACAGUUUUCAGAUGCUUCAAGUGUUGUGAACAGAGACUUGUUUGGAUUAUGCAUUUCUCAGCUAGACUAAAUAAAUGCUAGCAAUGGAUACGUGCAAACAUGUUGGGCAGCUGCAGCUUGCUCAAGACCAUUCCAGCCUCAACCCUCAGAAAUGGCACUGUGUGGACUGCAACACGACCGAGUCCAUUUGGGCUUGCCUUAGCUGCUCCCAUGUUGCCUGUGGAAGAUAUAUUGAAGAGCAUGCACUCAAGCACUUUCAAGAAAGCAGUCAUCCUGUUGCAUUGGAGGUGAAUGAGAUGUACGUUUUUUGUUACCUUUGUGAUGAUUAUGUUCUGAAUGAUAACACAACUGGAGACCUGAAGUUACUACGACGUACAUUAAGUGCCAUCAAAAGUCAAAAUUAUCACUGCACAACUCGUAGUGGGAGGUUUUUACGGUCCAUGGGUACAGGUGAUGAUUCUUAUUUCUUACAUGACGGUGCCCAAUCUCUGCUUCAAAGUGAAGAUCAACUGUAUACUGCUCUUUGGCACAGGAGAAGGAUACUAAUGGGUAAAAUCUUUCGAACAUGGUUUGAACAAUCACCCAUUGGAAGAAAAAAGCAAGAAGAACCAUUUCAGGAAAAAAUAGUAGUAAAAAGAGAAGUAAAGAAAAGACGGCAGGAAUUGGAGUAUCAAGUUAAAGCAGAAUUGGAAAGUAUGCCUCCAAGAAAGAGUUUACGUUUACAAGGGCUCGCUCAGUCGACCAUAAUAGAAAUAGUUUCUGUUCAGGUGCCAGCACAAACGCCAGCAUCACCAGCAAAAGAUAAAGUACUCUCUACCUCAGAAAAUGAAAUAUCUCAAAAAGUCAGUGACUCCUCAGUUAAACGAAGGCCAAUAGUAACUCCUGGUGUAACAGGAUUGAGAAAUUUGGGAAAUACUUGCUAUAUGAAUUCUGUUCUUCAGGUGUUGAGUCAUUUACUUAUUUUUCGACAAUGUUUUUUAAAGCUUGAUCUGAACCAAUGGCUGGCUAUGACUGCUAGCGAGAAGACAAGAUCUUGUAAGCAUCCACCAGUCACAGAUACAGUAGUAUAUCAAAUGAAUGAAUGUCAGGAAAAAGAUACAGGUUUUGUUUGCUCCAGACAAUCAAGUCUGUCAUCAGGACUAAGUGGUGGAGCAUCAAAAGGUAGAAAGAUGGAACUUAUUCAGCCAAAGGAGCCAACUUCACAGUACAUUUCUCUUUGUCAUGAAUUGCAUACUUUGUUCCAAGUCAUGUGGUCUGGAAAGUGGGCGUUGGUCUCACCAUUUGCUAUGCUACACUCAGUGUGGAGACUCAUUCCUGCCUUUCGUGGUUACGCCCAACAAGACGCUCAGGAAUUUCUUUGUGAACUUUUAGAUAAAAUACAACGUGAAUUAGAGACAACUGGUACCAGUUUACCAGCUCUUAUCCCCACUUCUCAAAGGAAACUCAUCAAACAAGUUCUGAAUGUUGUAAAUAACAUUUUUCAUGGACAACUUCUUAGUCAGGUUACAUGUCUUGCAUGUGACAACAAAUCAAAUACCAUAGAACCUUUCUGGGACUUGUCAUUGGAGUUUCCAGAAAGGUAUCAAUGCAGUGGAAAAGAUAUUGCUUCCCAGCCAUGUCUGGUUACUGAAAUGUUGGCCAAAUUUACAGAAACUGAAGCUUUAGAAGGAAAAAUCUACGUAUGUGACCAGUGUAACUCAAAGCGUAGAAGGUUUUCCUCCAAACCAGUUGUACUCACAGAAGCCCAGAAACAACUUAUGAUAUGCCACCUACCUCAGGUUCUCAGACUGCACCUCAAACGAUUCAGGUGGUCAGGACGUAAUAACCGAGAGAAGAUUGGUGUUCAUGUUGGCUUUGAGGAAAUCUUAAACAUGGAGCCCUAUUGCUGCAGGGAGACCCUGAAAUCCCUCAGACCAGAAUGCUUUAUCUAUGACUUGUCCGCGGUGGUGAUGCACCAUGGGAAAGGAUUUGGCUCAGGGCACUACACUGCCUACUGCUAUAAUUCUGAAGGAGGGUUCUGGGUACACUGCAAUGAUUCCAAACUAAGCAUGUGCACUAUGGAUGAAGUAUGCAAGGCUCAAGCUUAUAUCUUGUUUUAUACCCAACGAGUUACUGAGAAUGGACAUUCUAAACUUUUGCCUCCAGAGCUCCUGUUGGGGAGCCAACAUCCCAAUGAAGACGCUGAUACCUCGUCUAAUGAAAUCCUUAGCUGAUCCAAAGACAAUGGGGUUUUCUUCCUGUGAUUUAUAUAUAUACUUUUUAAAAGACUGAUGUACCAUUUUAAACUUCAUUUUUUCUUGUGAAUCAGUGUAUACUACAUUUAUACAUUUUAUAUCUAACAAUUUUUUUUUUUACAAAGUAUAAAUGUAUAUAUCAACUGAAGGUAACUACUUUUUUCAUAUUUGGAGUUUUAAACUUUUGGUGUUUACCUCAGACUGAUGUUACCUCUUUUAUAUUUUUAUGUCUUAAUUGGCUCGGAUGAUGAACUUGUGCAAUCUUCUACCAACAAAGUUCAAGUGGCAUCAUUUUAUAUACAUGUAUCUUUUUCAGGUAUUUUCUAUACAAAUUCUUAAUAGAUGGAAAAUUAGACUCUACUUUGGUCACUAAUAGUCUUUCAUUUGUAUAUUGAAGUUACCUUGCCCCUUGGAGUUAUUGAAGUGACAUGUCAAGGUAUCACCUAAAUAUUCUUCAGUCACACUCACUGGUAUUUCUGAGGCUUUGUGUGUUAACAGGCCUUGUAAUUGACAUUAUUUUGGUUAAUGUAACCCCAAAAUUGCUUUAGUAAUUGCUCUUUGGCAUAGUCAAACUAUAAAUGAAAAUGGCAGCUUUACAAAUAGUAUAUUUAAGUGAACUCUGGAACUAUGGACAUGAAAAAAAUGAUGGCUGGGAUUUAUGAUUUUUGUCUGGCAGCAAACAGGUUUGUCCAGAAGUCUAAUAAUUAAGCAGUCAUAAAAAGUCUGAAUUUAGUAAACCAGUGUAUGAUGUUAUUCAAAUAGUUUACCUUGGGUAUGAGUUCAUUUUAUAAUGUCUGAUGACAUUAGAUCUCUUAAAACUUUAUGUAUUUUUUUUAGUUCAAAGGAAUAGAGUCUUGAAGAGAAAAAAUUAUAGGGCAGAAAAGAUAAGUGUUCAAAAUUGGCAACUGGACUAUUAUUAUGUCUAGCAUCUCAUUCUAAAUAACUAAAGCUUGAUUUACUCUUGCUAGGAUUAUGUGACUACUAGGUAGGAGCCUCUUAAAACACUGGCCCUGAGCAUUAAAAAAAAAAAAAAAAACUAAAAGCUAUCUAUCUAAACUUGCACAAAAAAAAAUACAGUGUGAGUCACUCUUUUUCUUCUUCUGAUAAUCUCACUGGGUUUCUUUAAAGUCCUGUUGCUGCUAACUUUAUCUUAUUUGGAGAGGGUAGAAUCAACUAAUCUCUGUAGACCAGCUAUGUAUCUAAGCUCUGUUAACCACAGGAAGAUCAUGUAUCCCUUUUUUAUAAGUGGGUUUAUUUGCAGGUUGAAGUCUUAGUGAAAGAUAGUAUCCUGUAGAAUGCUGUUCACCACUAGUGAUCAUCUGUUAAGUACAAACUUGAAAGAGGUCUCUACCAAUAAAUUUUUCUUAAAUUUCACAAAACAAGUCAUCUGGGUUAGCUGAUAGUGAGGUGCAGUGAGACUUUUAUCACUGAAUAGACAAAUCAUUUGUGCCGAAAAUACAUCUGGAAUAUUAAAUGGCUAUGUUUAAAAUUGUUCAUAAUACCUAUGCAAGUUGUUACCUCAACUGUUACACACUUCUUAAUACCUCAUUAAAAAUUUACAUGGUCAAGAUAA